GGAAGGCACGGCGCUCAGCUCAGGACCGCGCGCCGUGGUCUGAGGUCCGCGGCAGGGUCCCGCAUGGCGGCGCACAGGAAGCACGUGUUUGUGGAGAAGGUGCUGCAGAGACUUUUUCCUCCUGUUCCAAGUGGCCAAGGAAAGAGGGAACCCCAGACGCUGGCCGUCCAAAAUCCACCAAAGAAAGUGACCUCUGAGAAAGUGAGCCAGAAACAUGCUGAGCCUUUGACAGACACUGGCUCUGAGACCCCGACUGCCCGACGGCUCUACACUGCCAGCGGGCCUCCUGAGGGCUACGUCCCCUGUUGGCCGGAGCCCAGCAGCUGUGGGAGCCCCGAGAACGCCUCCAGCGGGGAUGACACAGAAGAUCAGGAUCCUCAUGACCAGCCAAAGAGAAGAAGAAUUAGGAAGCAUAAAUCAAAGAAAAAAUUUAAAAAUCCCAAUAAUGUUCUUAUAGAACAAGCAGAAUUAGAGAAACAGCAGAGUCUGUUACAGGAGAAAUCUCAGCGACAGCACACAGAUGGCACCACAAUAAGCAAAAAUAAAAAAAGGAAACUGAAAAAGAAACAGCAAAUUAAAAGGAAGAAAGCAGCCGGCUUGGCAGCAAAGGCUGCUGGUGUCAGUUUCAUGUACCAGCCCGAGGACAGCAGCAAUGAAGGGGAAGGCGUGGGAGAGGCUUGUGAGGAGGAUGGUGUGGACACCAGCGAGGAAGACCCGACACUGGCCGGGGAGGAAGACGUUAAAGAUACCAGGGAGGAAGAUGGUGCGGACGCUAGCGAGGAAGACCUGACACGGGCCAGGCAGGAAGAGGGUGCGGACGCCAGUGAGGAAGAUCCGACACCGGCCGGGGAGGAAGACGUUAAAGACGCCAGGGAGGAGGACGGUGUGGACACCAUUGAGGAAGACCUGACACGGGCCGGGGAGGAAGACGGUAAAGACACCAGGGAGGAGGACGGUGCGGACGCCAGCGAGGAAGACCCGACAUGGGCUGGGGAGGAAGAGGGUGCAGACUCCGGGGAGGAGGACGGUGCAGACGCCAGCGAGGAAGAUGAUACAAUUACCAAUGAAAAGGCACACAGUAUUCUAAAUUUUUUGAAGUCAACACAGGAAAUGUAUUUUUAUGACGGUGUCUCCAGAGAUGCAGCUUCAGCUGCCCUCGCAGAUGCCGCUGAGGAGCUGCUGGACCGCCUUGCGUCACACAGCAUGCUGCCCUCAGACGUGUCCAUCCUGUACCACAUGAAAACGCUGCUGCUCCUGCAAGAUACUGAGAGAUUGAAGCAUGCUCUGGAAAUGUUCCCAGAACAUUGCACGAUGCCUCCUGCUUUUAUUGGCUCUUGUCGAAAUCAAAUUGGAAGAUCUUCAGUCCCAGCUGCACCCAACGUGGAAAAGUAUUCCAGGUCCAUCCCCAAGGAACCAACACCGAUGACAUGGACUCAGGAAUCUUAUAACCUACGUGGACUCUUUCCAUCCGUACAUUGUCGUGCACAUGCCACUCAUCACCUGGCGUGCCCAGAUCCUCGCAGGGCAACACCCUGUGAUAAUUCCAGGCACGACCGGCCCACCUGCCCACCGCACUGUAACGGAAGCUGUAUCUCAAGCAGGCCUCCUCUCCGAAGAACAUGGCCCGUGCUGGCUGAGGGUCUGAACGUGCCCAAGCGUGGCUGUCUGGUGCUGAGCUUCCCAUCGAGCCCCAGGAAUGUUGGAACUAGCCCAAAGCCCUGUAAGCAAGGUCUUAGGACACUGGGAGGCUCUGAAAUCACAGAUGUAAGUAAAAGAUAAGAAACGCCAAGGCAAGGGCCAGGCGCCCCACACGUGGUAGGAGCUUCUGCAGGAUGCUGGGCCCUUCCUCAGCAGGUGCUUUGCCUGGGUUGUGCUCCCGCAGCCUGACUGCUGCCCCAGGUCACCGAUGUAAAUGACUCAGGACCUCCUAGAGAACAGGCUUCUGUGUAAAGUCAUUAUUUUGCUUCCUCACCAAAUCCUGCCCCUGCAAAGCAGUCCACAGAACUUAGUGGCUUGUUAAAGGUGCAUCUGUUGAAUCAAAGUCCUCAGCAGAAAGCCUGGCCCCUGCAUUUUGUUCGGCUGCCUGCAGUGGCCAGAGCAGGCUACAUGUUGAGAGCAGGACCCUGGCUGCUGUGCUCUCGCACGGCUGGUGACUACAGCGGGGUCUGGACGUCAGGCAAGCACUGUUUGACUCCCGGCUGCUCCACUCCCCAACUGAGCAGCCGUGGCUUCUGUGGUAGGAACUGCCAGAUGCCCCCCAGCUUUCCUCCUGCUCCCAGGCACACGGUGGGGCUGUGUUGCCCUACCCCACUAGGUUCUGUGGCCCUGUGAGGUCAUCCUCACAGCUGAGCACCCCACACAGCUUCCCUGCCCUCUUCUUUUGAAUUCAGCAUCUGCAGUGGCCAUGAGCAGAGCCAGACAGCAGGAGCUGGGCCCUGGACGACUCCACGGGAGAAACAGCCACAACAGGCAUGUGGGGCUCUGAUUGUAGGCGAGCCGGCUCUGCAGGGAUACAGAAAUCCACCCCAGGAGUGGCGAGCUGCCCUAGCAAAACCCCAAGCACGUGGUGAGGAUGGAAUGCUGGGCAGCAUGAGAGGAGACACAUGGGGCUAGAGGAACGUGUAGCCCAGGAGCCGCAGAAUCAGGCACAGCUGUGGCUUUUACCCACUCAGGCCACUGAGGUCCCAGGGUGGCAGCUCUGGGAAGCAGCUAGGAAUGCAGGAUGCCGGGGACGAGGCUGUUGGUUGCAGAACCCCACCGGGUGUUUCACAGAAUGAGUGUGGCCAGAUCCAGCCUGUUUCCAGCAGGGCUGACACAACUACAGCCCCGAUGGGCCCAGAGAAGCCACAGUGGCUGCAGAGAGAAGAGAGAAGCAGAAACGUGUCGUUAGCCUUCAGGCAACAGGAAGCAGCCCUGGUGUGGUCACUGCACAAGGAACAGGCUUGGUGAGCUGGUUUGGACGCCUUCGGUGCGUUUGCAAUCUGGCUUAAAGUCCUGAACCAACCCUCCGACCCUGCAGAAAGUGGACUGUGCAGGCUGGGAAAUGCUGAGAAGGAAGUCCUGAACCAACCCUCCGACCCUGCAGAAAGUGGGCUGUGCAGGCUGGGAAAUGCUCAGAAGGUGACUCCCAACACGUGGCCUGGAAGUCAUGGAGGAUUCUGGACGGGAGGGCAGAGCCCAGAGCAUCCCUCCUGGCCCCUCAGGGGAGCACGUCUGGGGCCUCAUCAGGGAGCUGCCUGCCGAGGCCAGGUCUGCACCGUUCCUCCCCAGAGGUCACAGUGUCGGAGGCUGCACAGCCACUGCAGCAGCGACCCUUUAUUUGGACUGCGCUUUUGUUGUAGGUGUCCUGUCUGCUGUUGUGCAUUUGGUGGGACAGUGCUGAGGGUUUGGUGGACAGGGCUGAGGGUAAGUGGAGGGCUUGUGCUCAGUGCACAGGCCUCCGUCCGUGAGGAGACUCUGUUGGGCCCACGUGGGGCAGAACCCAGGCAGAUGCCCCGAUUCUGAGCUAAAGUCGGGAGAGGAAGGCACUCUGGGCCGUCUCCUUUGGGAACAGCUAAGAGUAUUUUCUAUGAGGGAGGAACGAUGAAAAGGCAUCCCGUGACCAGAAGGACAGUCUCUAGCAGAAACCAUCAAUGAUUUCCACACAUCCGAGGCCUUGGCUCCCUGGUUGUGGCUGCACCUAGUUCCCAGUUGACGUGCAACCCCACGUGGCCACGCAGCUGAGCUUCAGGGAGGCUGUGAACGCCCAGCUCGGCUCAGGGCCAUGGAGGUGGUUGGGGCGCAGGGAUUCAGCUCGGCCCAGGGCAGUGGAGGUGGCCGGGGCGCAGGGAUUCAGCCGCCUUAGAGCGCGCCAGACAUUAGCCCCAGGCUGAGUGUUUUCCACAGAGAAUGCUAUUAACAGGAUCCCAGCUUUUGCCUCUCUGAGAGAUGGCAUGAAGGAGCCCACAGCCUCGUUGCACCAGGUGGCCCUGGCAAGGUGCAGCUUUGGGCUGUUUCUGCCGAGGCGGAGGCCUUCUCGCCCUGGUUGAACGGCUCGCAGGAUGAGGAAUCACCGCACCUGCCGCGUAAGAGCCGCUUGCAAGUUAAAUGGGGUGAACCUUUGAAGGACCUGCUGCGUUUUGGAUCCAGAGUUGGUUGAACACAAACUUUGGUGAGCCAACCGUCCCUGCUGUGGGGUGCAGCACGCAUGUGGACCACAGACUCACGGACACACACACACACGCUGGGGGAGCGUCGGCCCCACUCGAUGGUGACAAGUGUGCUCACACCCCGUUGCUAGAGCCUCCAGGGACCCUGCUUGGGAAGCCAGUCAUGACAGGUGAGCGUGAGGGUGCAGGGACGGGUUGCUGGGAGUCCCUGGACACAUCCCGCAGGGUCCUCUGGCAGGUCGGGGCCGGGCCGGCUGGCCACUACGUCCAGGUCGACCACAGCUGUGCCGCCUGCGGGCUGUGAUCUGGGCUCCCAAGACCACCCAUGUAUGAGGGAGGACAGGUGGGGACUGGGUGGGGCGUUGGUGCAGGUGAACGCCCUAGACAGCCCCUCUCACAGCCAGCCUUAGCUGUCACUAUUGUUAGUGGUGAUGAGCCCUGCGGGGACUUUGGAGGGAAGCUCAGGCUGGUCCCAACGGCCCGGGCUUGGCGUUUAUCCGUUAUACCCGGAUAAACCCGUGUGGGGGGCUCCAUCACAGACUUAGACGCCUGUUUUCUCUAUGGACCUGACGCAACUCAAGGGAAACUCAUAAGCUCGGAUGUGUAUUUCCUGGCUCUUUCCUGAGGCUGAGGGGCCUGUCCUCGGGGGGUUUCCUGAACAGAGGUCACCAUGAAAUGGUCACAGGGAGAGGCAGAUGCGGCCACGCCCACUCCUGGUGAGGUGCUUUUUUUUUUUAGCUGAGUGGCUCCGGCAACCCCUUGAGUCCACGUCCCUGAGUGUCCAAAGCCUGGGACACCCCCAGGUGCGGUCUGAAGCCACGGGUGGCCAGGCUGCAGGAGGGAACUCCGACGGCCACCGUGAUCCCUUUCCCUCCUUCCUUCCCCAGAGGCACCAAGAGGGCAGCCACAGCCCCAGCUCCCAAGGUCCUUGCGGGACGCUGCCCUGUUACCUGAUUCCUGGAAGGAGAGAGGCUAUAGAGCUGCAAAACUCUUAAGAGACAAAAAAGAACCUUUCCCUGAUUUUCUGAUGCUUGACCUGGGCUGCUCAGCGGGGUUUGGAAGUGCAGAGGCUUCCGGUCGCCAAGGUCAUCCCGCGUGGGACUCAGUGUCACAGCGGCCCCUCUCACACCCGGGACCAGCUGAGUGGGUGCCCACGGCAGCCCCCCACCCAUCGUGGGGGCUGGUCCGGCUGCUCCGCCAGCUGUCCUUCUGCGCACACAGUGGGCACCUACUGCACGCAUGGCACUGUGCUUAGAGCUGGAGUGAGCCGCAAGCAAACCUGCUGUUGAAGGUGCCCGCCCGACGGGGCCGCCCUGAGCAUGGGUGUGCAGACGUAUCCUCGAGACCCUGUUCAGUGUUUUGGGUGUACGCCCAGGAGACGAAUUGCUGGAUGCUGUGGCAAUUCUAUGUUUACUUGUUUGAGGAGCUUCCAUGGUAGCUGCACCAUUUCACAUUCCCGCCAACAGUGCACGAGGGUUCCAAGCGCUCCACGACGCUCGCUCGUUGCCUUUGUGUUUUGUUUCUAUAGCAGCCAUCCCAACGGGUGAGGUGAGCACCGCUUCGUGGAUUUAUCAGCUACUUGUGUGUCUUCUUUGGAUAAAUGUUGAUUCAAGUCCUUUGGCCAUUUUUGAAUCAGGGUUUUUUUUGUUUGUUUUUUUUUUUUUUUUUUGAGUUUUAGGAGUUCUCUAUAGAUUCUGGUUUUUAACCCCUUACUAGAUGCAUGAUUUGUAAAUAUUUUCCCCAUUGUGUGCUCUGCCGUUUUACUCUUAAUGUCAUUUGAUGGACGAAAUGUUUUUGUUUCCACGCAGUCCCGCUGUCUGCUUUUUCUGUUGUCGCCUGGGCCUUUGGUGUCACCUUCAAGAAGUCACUGCCAAAUCCAACAUCGUGGCAGUUUUCCCUGUGUUUCCUUAUGAGAGGUUUAGGUCUCACAUUUAGGUCUUUGAUGUACUUUGCACUGAUUUUUGUCAGCUGUAAAGUAGGGGCCAAUUUCAUUCCUUUGCGUGUGGAUGUCCUGUUUCCCAGCACCAUCGGUGGAAGCGGCUGUCUUUUCCCAUUGAGGAGUCCUGCCAUCCUGGCACCUGUGCCAAAGCCCAUUCGACCUUGAGUUUGAGGGUUUAUUUCUGGGUCCUCGCCUCUGUUCCCUUGGUCCAUACACCACCUUUAUAUCAGGACGGUGAUGCUUUCAUUCCUGUGGCUUGGCAGUAAAAUUUUGAAUCAGGAAAUGUGAGUCUCCAGCUUCGUUCUUUUUAGGAUUGUUUUGGGUAAUCAGGAACCCUUGAGAUUCCAUGUGAAUUUAGGGUGGGUUUUUCUGUUUCUCUGAGAAAUAUCCUUGAGAUUCUCCCAGGAAGAUAUAUUGUUUUGAGGGCUUUAAAACUCCCUAUAAAUAUUGCUGUACUUUGGGGGCCCUUUUCUUCCCACACUGUGUUUUUGAGAUUUACCCAUGCUGUUGUGAGUACCUCGCUGAAUGCAGCACAUACUGCAUCAUACAAGUGCAUCCUGAUCCAUUUCCCCUGACGGACGUGUUCAUUUUUUGUUAUGGCAAUGCUGCAAUACACGUUUUUAGCUGUGCCUCUUUGUGCUUGAAUGUGAGGGGUUUUCUAAGGUGUGAACCUCAGAACAGAGUCGCCAGGCCAUAGGGUGUGCACAGCCUCCGUCUGUCCUGGGCGGCCCCACGCGGGCUCCACACUGGUUUCCGUCUGUCCUGGGCAGCACCACGGUGGCUCCACACUGGUUUCCACACUGGUUUCCGUCUGUCCUGGGCGGCCCCGCGCGGGCCCCACACUGGUUGUGCGUUUCUCAGGCCACCAGCAGCGUCCAAGAGCUCUGGCCGAUCUGCCUCCCUCCCUGCGUCUCGGCAUCUUUGUCUGGCACUGCUGAUGGUUUUGCCUAAACGGCUCUUUGCUGUGGGGCAUCCUGUGCACCGUGGGACGUCUUGUGCACUGUGGGGUGUUGAGCCGCAUCCGUGGUCUCCACCCACAGAUGACAACGACACCCCCAGCUAUGAAACCAGAAAUGACUCCACACAUUGCCAAAUGUCCCCCAGGGCAAAGUCACCCACUUGGGCGUUAUGUUACCCACUGAUGAUCUGAAUUUUUGUCCAUUUCACCUGUCUGAGUUUGUGUGUCUCUGAGCACUGGUGGGACUGAGCGUGUCCGUGGCUUGUGGCCACUCCUGCUUCCUGUUUGUGAAUUUUAUGUUCAUAACGUCUGCCCCUUUCUUUGGGUUUUUCACUUUAUUCUUAUUAUUUUGUAAAUUCCUUAAGUAUUCUGGAUACUUACCUUUUGUUAUUCUAUUCUAGUAGUCACUGUCCCCAAAACAAUGUUCAUAAAUUUGUUCUUAUAAAGAUGAGAAAUAAAAAACAUUGAAUUUUA